GUUAGUUGCUUGUGGUAACUAAGGCAGGUGGCAUACAUCUCAGAACGUGGAGAAUGAUGGUAUGCUUUCUGAGUUAACAUGUUGAACUGUUUUGCUUUUCUAAAAAUUUUCCUAGUAACAUUUUCUUGAUGAUAUGAGAGUGGAUAUCAAUGCCUCACAGAAACAAGAGGUGGAACAUGUGAAUGAAUCGUCUUGGAACUAGAUUAUGAGCACUGGUUCUUUUUAAAGGGAUGUGCAAGAGGCAGCCUUGGCAAGAAAACUUGCUGCAUAAUCUUACAUGGACUAAAGAUGAAACUUUAAACCGCAAAUCAGCUUUGAGUGAACUUUGACAGAAGAUGUUUCGACAGUUUUAUCUCUGGACAUGUUUAGCUUCAGGGAUCAUCCUGGGCUCUCUCUUUGAAAUCUGCUUGGGCCAGUAUGAUGAUGAUUGCAAACUAGCUAGGGGAGGACCACCAGCUACCAUAGUUGCUAUUGAUGAAGAAAGUCGGAAUGGUACAAUUCUGGUGGACAACAUGCUGAUCAAAGGGACUGCUGGAGGACCAGACCCCACCAUAGAACUUUCUUUAAAGGAUAAUGUGGAUUACUGGGUGUUGAUGGAUCCUGUUAAGCAAAUGCUUUUCCUGAACAGCACCGGAAGAGUUCUGGAUAGAGAUCCACCGAUGAACAUACACUCCAUUGUGGUGCAGGUCCAGUGCAUCAACAAAAAAGUGGGCACUAUUAUCUACCAUGAAGUGCGAAUAGUGGUGAGAGACAGGAAUGACAACUCACCCACUUUCAAGCAUGAAAGCUACUAUGCCACAGUGAAUGAGCUCACUCCAGUUGGUACCACAAUAUUCACAGGAUUUUCAGGAGACAAUGGAGCUACAGAUAUAGAUGAUGGACCAAAUGGACAGAUAGAGUAUGUUAUUCAGUAUAAUCCAGAUGAUCCGACAUCCAAUGACACCUUUGAAAUUCCCCUAAUGUUGACUGGAAAUAUAGUGUUAAGGAAGAGGCUCAACUAUGAAGAUAAGACUCGCUACUUUGUCAUAAUCCAAGCUAAUGACCGUGCCCAAAAUCUGAAUGAGAGGCGAACCACCACCACCACUCUCACAGUGGAUGUUCUGGAUGGAGAUGACUUGGGUCCAAUGUUUCUUCCUUGUGUCCUUGUGCCAAACACUCGUGAUUGCCGUCCACUCACUUAUCAAGCUGCCAUACCUGAGUUGAGAACUCCGGAAGAACUGAACCCCAUUAUUGUUACGCCACCAAUCCAAGCCAUUGAUCAGGACCGGAAUAUUCAACCGCCAUCAGAUAGGCCAGGAAUCCUCUAUUCCAUCCUUGUUGGGACUCCUGAGGAUUACCCACGAUUUUUCCAUAUGCAUCCUAGGACAGCAGAACUUAGUCUCCUGGAGCCAGUAAACAGAGACUUUCACCAGAAAUUUGAUUUGGUUAUUAAGGCUGAACAAGACAAUGGUCAUCCUCUUCCUGCCUUUGCCGGUCUACACAUUGAAAUACUGGAUGAAAACAAUCAAAGUCCAUAUUUUACAAUGCCCAGUUAUCAAGGCUAUAUCCUGGAAUCUGCCCCAGUGGGAGCAACCAUUUCGGACAGUCUCAAUUUGACUUCACCUUUAAGAAUAGUAGCUCUGGACAAGGACAUAGAAGAUACAAAAGACCCAGAGCUUCACCUUUUUCUGAAUGACUACACCUCAGUCUUCACCGUCACACAGACUGGUAUUACUCGCUACCUCACCUUACUUCAACCAGUGGACAGGGAAGAACAGCAAACUUACACCUUUUCGAUAACAGCAUUUGAUGGUGUACAAGAAAGUGAGCCAGUCAUCGUCAAUAUUCAAGUGAUGGAUGCAAAUGAUAACACGCCAACCUUCCCUGAAAUAUCCUAUGAUGUGUAUGUUUAUACAGACAUGAGACCUGGGGACAGUGUCAUACAGCUCACUGCAGUCGACGCAGACGAAGGGUCAAAUGGGGAGAUCACAUAUGAAAUCCUUGUUGGGGCUCAGGGAGACUUCAUCAUCAAUAAAACAACAGGGCUUAUCACCAUCGCUCCAGGGGUGGAAAUGAUAGUCGGGCGGACUUACGCACUCACGGUCCAAGCAGCGGAUAAUGCUCCUCCUGCAGAGCGAAGGAACUCCAUCUGCACUGUGUAUAUUGAAGUGCUUCCACCAAAUAAUCAAAGCCCUCCUCGCUUCCCACAGCUGAUGUAUAGCCUUGAAAUUAGUGAAGCCAUGAGGGUUGGUGCUGUUUUAUUAAAUCUACAGGCAACUGAUCGAGAGGGAGACUCAAUAACAUAUGCCAUUGAGAAUGGAGAUCCUCAGAGAGUUUUUAAUCUUUCAGAAACCACGGGGAUUCUAACCUUAGGGAAAGCACUGGACAGGGAAAGCACUGAUCGCUACAUUCUGAUCAUCACAGCUUCAGAUGGCAGGCCAGAUGGGACCUCAACUGCCACAGUAAACAUAGUGGUGACAGAUGUCAAUGACAAUGCUCCAGUGUUUGAUCCUUAUCUGCCAAGAAAUUUAUCUGUGGUGGAAGAAGAAGCCAAUGCCUUUGUGGGUCAAGUAAAAGCAACAGACCCUGAUGCUGGAAUAAAUGGUCAAGUGCACUACAGUUUGGGUAACUUUAAUAAUCUUUUUCGUAUCACAUCCAAUGGGAGCAUUUACACAGCAGUGAAGCUUAACAGAGAAGUCAGGGACUACUAUGAACUUGUUGUUGUGGCAACAGAUGGAGCAGUACACCCUCGUCAUUCAACUCUAACCUUGGCCAUCAAGGUUUUGGACAUUGAUGAUAACAGUCCUGUGUUCACCAAUUCAACAUACACUGUCCUUGUUGAAGAGAAUUUGCCAGCUGGGACUACCAUCCUUCAAAUAGAGGCCAAAGAUGUCGACCUUGGAGCAAAUGUGUCUUACCGGAUAAGAAGCCCAGAAGUGAAGCACUUUUUUGCACUACAUCCAUUUACAGGAGAACUAUCGCUUUUAAGGAGUUUAGAUUAUGAGGCAUUUCCAGACCAAGAAGCAAGUAUCACUUUUCUGGUAGAGGCCUUUGAUAUUUAUGGAACAAUGCCACCUGGUAUUGCUACUGUCACAGUGAUUGUAAAGGAUAUGAAUGAUUAUCCUCCUGUCUUUAGUAAACGAAUAUACAAAGGGAUGGUGGCUCCGGAUGCAGUCAAGGGUACACCUAUCACAACAGUUUAUGCUGAAGAUGCAGACCCUCCUGGAUUACCUGCAAGUCGUGUGAGGUAUAGAGUAGAUGAUGUACAGUUUCCUUACCCUGCCAGUAUUUUUGAAGUGGAAGAAGAUUCUGGAAGAGUAAUAACACGAGUCAAUCUUAAUGAAGAACCUACAACAAUUUUUAAGUUGGUGGUGGUUGCUUUUGAUGAUGGGGAGCCUGUGAUGUCCAGCAGUGCCACAGUGAAGAUUCUUGUCUUACAUCCUGGUGAGAUCCCACGCUUCACACAGGAGGAAUAUAGACCUCCUCCAGUAAGUGAACUUGCCACCAAAGGGACCAUGGUUGGUGUAAUUUCUGCUGCUGCCAUUAAUCAAAGUAUUGUGUACUCCAUUGUUUCAGGAAAUGAAGAAGAUACAUUUGGAAUUAAUAACAUCACAGGUGUUAUCUAUGUGAAUGGACCUCUGGAUUAUGAGACCAGGACAAGCUAUGUACUUCGAGUCCAAGCUGAUUCCCUGGAAGUGGUCCUUGCCAAUCUCCGAGUUCCUUCAAAAAGCAAUACAGCUAAAGUAUACAUUGAGAUUCAGGAUGAAAAUAAUCAUCCCCCAGUGUUUCAGAAAAAAUUCUACAUCGGAGGUGUAUCUGAAGAUGCAAGAAUGUUUACUUCUGUACUCAGAGUGAAGGCUACUGAUAAAGAUACUGGCAAUUAUAGUGUCAUGGCCUACAGACUCAUAAUACCACCAAUUAAAGAGGGAAAAGAAGGAUUUGUAGUGGAAACAUAUACAGGGCUUAUCAAAACUGCUAUGCUCUUCCAUAAUAUGAGGAGAUCCUACUUCAAGUUUCAAGUUAUUGCAACUGACGACUAUGGGAAGGGACUGAGCGGCAAAGCCGAUGUACUCGUCUCCGUGGUCAAUCAGCUGGAUAUGCAAGUCAUUGUUUCCAAUGUGCCUCCUACUCUAGUGGAAAAAAAGAUAGAAGAUCUUACAGAGAUCUUGGAUCGCUAUGUUCAGGAACAAAUUCCUGGUGCCAAGGUCGUAGUGGAGUCCAUUGGAGCUCGCCGGCAUGGAGAUGCCUUUUCCCUAGAAGAUUACACCAAAUGUGACUUGACUGUCUAUGCAAUUGACCCCCAAACCAACAGAGCCAUCGAUAGAAAUGAGCUUUUUAAAUUUUUGGAUGGCAAACUACUUGAUAUCAAUAAAGACUUUCAGCCGUAUUAUGGGGAAGGAGGACGCAUUCUGGAGAUCCGGACUCCAGAGGCAGUGACCAGCAUUAAAAAGAGAGGAGAAAGUCUAGGAUACACAGAAGGGGCCUUGUUGGCUCUGGCCUUCAUCAUCAUCCUCUGCUGCAUUCCUGCCAUCUUGGUGGUUUUGGUCAGCUACAGACAGUUUAAAGUACGUCAAGCUGAGUGUACAAAGACUGCACGAAUUCAGGCCGCAUUACCCGCGGCUAAACCAGCAGUGCCGGCUCCUGCACCAGUGGCAGCGCCCCCGCCGCCGCCGCCGCCUCCGCCAGGUGCGCAUCUCUAUGAAGAACUUGGAGACAGCUCAAUUUGGAGUUUUUGUUGGCAGCUGGUCAUAUGCAUGAGAACUUGUGCUAUUUGGCGGACUCUGACAAGGAGAGGUUAUGGAUCAGAGCAACAGCAACUGCUGAGGCCCUCUCUUCUUAAACCAGAGGAAUUAUCCAUGGAGUCUGGAAUUGAUCCUGGCCAGGAAUAUGGACAAGAUUAUUACAGUUAUGAGCAUGGGUAUGAAAUGCCUCAAUAUGGGAGUCGCCGUCGAUUGUUACCACCAGCUGGACAGGAGGAAUAUGGUGAGGUGGUUGGUGAAGCUGAGGAAGAAUAUGAGGAGGAAGAGUGGGCAAGAAAAAGAAUGAUCAAGUUAGUUGUUGAUCGAGAGUAUGAAACCAGCUCAACUGGAGAAGACAGUGCUCCUGAAUGUCAGAGAAACCGUCUUCACCAUCCUAGUAUCCACAGUAAUAUCAACGGCAAUAUAUAUAUUGCACAGAAUGGUUCUGUGGUGAGAACCCGCCGUGCCUGCCUCACGGACAACUUAAAAGUUGCUUCCCCUGUUCGACUGGGAGGGCCCUUUAAGAAACUAGACAAGUUGGCAGUGACACAUGAGGAGAAUGUACCUCUGAACACAUUAUCAAAGGGGCCAUUUUCUACUGAAAAAAUGAAUGCAAGACCAACUCUGGUUACAUUUGCCCCUUGCCCUGUGGGGACUGACAAUACAGCGGUGAAGCCACUAAGGAACAGGCUGAAAAGCACAGUUGAACAGGAGUCCAUGAUUGACAGUAAGAACAUCAAGGAGGCUUUGGAAUUUCAUAGUGACCACACACAGUCUGAUGAUGAAGAGCUUUGGAUGGGCCCCUGGAACAACCUCCAUAUACCAAUGACAAAACUGUGACCAAUUUUUUAAAAGAUAUUUUAAUUAAUUUUUACUUACAUUUUUAAUAAACUGUGCUUUUUAUUGUCACUGAGAAAACAAUGUAUGGAAUUUAUAUCAUGCACACAAGCUAAAACUUUGAACAAUAUGCUUUAAAAUUUUAAGAGACAGAUUUGCACUCACAUUGUUAUCAAUUAAUCGUUUUUCCCAGAAAAUCCUUUUGGACAUACUUUCACUAAAUAACCUAUCGUUUAAACAUUUAGCUGUUUUGUUGGGUCUUGAAUUUUUGUUCAUUUUAAUAAACAAGAAAUAAUUACUAAAUAAUCAUUUAUAUUUUAUUGAUUAACAUAGAUUAUGCUUUAUUUCUAGCUCCACAAAACAUUUUUAGUACAUGUAAUUUUAUUUUCCAUAGCCAAAAGGGCAAAAAAGAAGUAAGAGGAUAUUUACAGGCAAUGAGUUUAUACAGCUGCUGUCUAUACUGCCCUAAUUUUUAAAAUGAAAGCUAGAAUUGCAAAGUAAAGUAAAUGAGGGAAUCACCUGUAAAUAAUUAAUUAUUUUAAAUCAUGAGCUUGUUUUCUUUCUUUAUUGUCCUGUAUAAAGGUUUUCACAUUUUACCAUAAAUACAUUUAUAUCUUGACCCUUUAGGAAACCACUUGAAGUCGUAUGUCUUUUUAUCAAUAUUAUUUACAAUAUUCUCUUGUCCCUUCAUCUCAUAUCAAAUAUGGUAGAUACUUUAGUUUAGUUUAAUCACUUGAGGUUAAAUAAUUGUUUGGAGCAACAUGGAAAUCUCACCCUUAGCAAAAGCUUUUAGGGAAGUGAGAAAGGUUCGAGUAAGCAGUAAUGCAUCUAGAACGACAAUUUCAUAAUGGAAGACAUGGUGAGGUUAGGGAAGUCUCACAUUAAUGUCACUAGACUUUAAUAGUUUGUAAACCCAGCAUAUCAGAGUAAAGGAAUUUGGCAGGGUUGAAAUGUAUAUAAUAUAUAAAGCUUAUAAAGGCUAUGAAUUCAUAACUUCAAAUGUUGUGUUUAACUUCUUCCAUUUUCAGGUUAUUUAUAGAAUAUUUUAAUGCACAUAUUUAUGUGCCUAAAAUCCAGAACCAGGAAAUCAUUGCCUGGGCAUUUUUUAAAAUCAAAGAACAUGGUCUUGAUUUUUUACCAUUGAACAAAGCACAGUGUUUCAUCAUAAGUAGAAAUGAAAACAGAAUAUCCUUUAAAAAACUUGCCUUGUGUGUUGCUUAUUUUCCAGAUGAUGUAAAAAGAAUGAAACAAUAUAGAUUAAGAGAAUUCAGAAUUCUAUUGAAUAUUACUUAGUAUGAUAUAGAUGUAGCUCACUUCAAAUUUUGCACAGUAUUGACCAAGUUCAGGUUUUAAUGAAAUUUCCUCAUGCAUGCUUAAUAUAUGGUUGAAGGACUGAAUAAUGCACUAUUAUUUAUUCCCCUCUUACAUGUUUCGCGUCUUAAAAAUUGUUUAUUAUUAUGCUAUUUCCUCAUUUCCAAAGUGAAUGAAUUGUACUGACAUAAACUUGCCGACUUGUAAGAGUAGUAUGUUUUUACUUCAGAUUUCCAAGAAAAUAUUUGAGAUCAAAUACAGUAACAUCUCAUCUACCUUAUUUUAUUGAGAAUUAAUGCAUUCCAUACCCUUGCCAAAAAAACAAAACAAAACAAACAAACAAAAAAAAACCUAGUGGCAUUAGCUAGAUUAGAAACGUAGAAUCAUGACCACACCUCCUGGCCUGCCAAACAAGCAUCCACAUUUUCAAAAGAUCCUAAGGUGGUUUAUAUGCACAUUAAAUUUUGGAAGCAAUGAAGUCCGGGGCUUAUUCCUUCAGGCACCAAAGCAAUGGUUUUUAGUAUAGGAUACUUUGUAUAGGAAUUAGAUUAAGCAUAUAUUUCCCUACUAAUUCAAUCAGAGGUCAUCGAAUAUAAUUUAAUAUUAUCUUGAUACCCCCAGAUCAUCUCAGUCAGCAUCCCUUGAUAUUCUCUCUAUAUACAGCUUCAUGGCUGCGUUUUUGUCCUUUGAUUUCUGGCUGUGACAUUUAACUUAUUCUGUUGUUGUGCCUUUCUCACAUUUUUUUCUUUCAGUUUAUAGCUUCUAGUAUCCUGAUGGGAAAGUUUGUGUUUUUUGUUUGUUUUCUUAAUGUUGAAAAAUCAUGAAGCUUAAGAUGGGAAUUAGGUACACGGAUUCAACCAAAUGUUUUGCGACUCUUAGACGCUUUCUUUGGUUACCAGUAGAUUUGGAAAUAUGAUGUUGGCAGAAGUCUAGUGGCCUGACAUAUGAGAUGUCACUGUAUUUUAAACUACAUUUUUUAUGAGAAAAUAUGCAAAAUUUUACAAGCCACUUAGCAGACACAUUUCAGUAAUUUAAACUUGAUCAUUUCAGUAAAAACAAUCAUGAGGUCAAUCAUCUGUUACUUAAUGGAGAUAGUAUAAAGAGAAGCAGAAUUUACACAGAGCAACCAAACCAAAUAUUUGGUCAGUAUAUUUUUGGGUAACGUAGAGCAGCAAAAUUAUUACUAACUAAAUAAAUCUGGAUCAAUUAAAUAGUUACUUUCAUAGAACUUUCACUAGUCUAUAAAUCCCUGACUCAGGAUUAAAACUGUGGAACCCAGAGGAAAUACCCAGGUAUGUUUAAUCUUAAGAAUACUUCAUAUAAAUAACGUUUCAAUGUAAAUAUUUAUAAAGAAAUUGGUUGUUAUUUUUCCUAGGAAGGUGUAGGAAGGUUUUCUUGUUGUUCUCAAUCAGCACUAGCUUCAAUCAGGCAGAAGAAACAGCAGGUCUUGGCUAAUCGAGGUGAGAACAGAAUGAUGUAAUGACUAAUAUUGCAACCCGUUGAUUUUAGAAGGUCUUGUGGGCAUUAAGGGAAAGCAGAGGAAGAAUGAGAAAAUAUGGUCAGAGUGACAUAGGACAUUUGUGACUUAAUGACCAUCGAAUCACAGGUGUUAAUCUCCCUCUCUCAAUUUGUCUUUCUCAUUAAUUACAGACUCUGAGAGUUGUCAUAGAAUUGCAACCGUAGGUUGGCCAAAACCAUCUUUUUAAAAUACAGAAGAAAGUUUGCCUUGAAUUUUAUAUGUGAUAUGUCAUUCAUGUUAUUUUACCACAUUGUUCACAGGGAUGUUAAAGACUAUUAUUUACUUAAGUGGUUGUUCCAAAGGUGAUUCAGUAGUUACCAUUAAAAUAUUAUUUAAAAACAUUUUUAUAUCAUAGAGCCAGAAGUAAUUGAAUAUUGACUCUCGAGGGAAGACAUUUUCUGUCUUUUAUUUCAUGAGCUUUGAUUUUUCUCUUUCUCUGCUUCACCUUCUGCACUUUAUACCUUAAGUGGGAUUUAUAUACCACUUGAAUUUAAUUAGCAAAAUAGGCAAAAAGUGCUAAUAAUCUAUUCUCAGGGCAGAUGCCUAUUGGUGCCUGCAAAUUACACAGCGAUAAGGCUGAAGGAUAGGUUCAAAAUAAUGUUGAGGACUUACACAUUUUAUAGAUAGUUUCUUUCUAUUCCCAAAUGGUAUGUGAAAUUUUUGUUCUAUUUUUUUUAUUGGUUUUCAAUAGUUAAUUUUGAUCUUUAUCAUAAGAAGCUUUAGUUAUAGACUGGUAUUUUUUUCAUUGCAAUCUACUUUAAAUUUAUGGUCAGUUAAGCACAUGUAUGGAAGAUUCGAACAUUGUCUAUAGUUUGAAAAAUCUAUCAACACCUUCACUGCUUUCCCAAUUUCUUUAUCCAAAUACCUGUUCUUCCUUAACAAAUAUUAUGUUACUGUAUAAGAAUCUGAAUUAGAAGUUUUAAGUUAAAAUGCAUUGUUAUUCACUACACAAUGUUUCAAAAAUAAAUUUUCAUUUGAAAA